AGCAUUAUCACCGGUGUCUCCAUUCAGUUAACUUGUCUUAGAGGCUCCAACAAACAAGACCAAGCCAGUGCCUAGCCGGAGGCGGGCGGCACGGGACCGUUUUCUAGUUUUUUUUUCUUUCUUCUUUUUCAACCUUGGCAAAGAGAUAACGCCCUGAACAACGAGGAGGCCUCAGGAUGGCCAUGGAGGUUUGGACGCCCGCUCCAAGCGCUGGUUAAAAAUAAUAUGGAGACGGCACGGGAUUUGGCCUCUAGAAAAUAUAGGUCCCAUUGAAGAUGUGCAGGCGUCUGCACACGGCGGUGUGGAGGAGAAUAUGACAUCAGAUAUUAUUUGGUCGAAGAUCUCAGUGAAUACCCAUCUGUCCAUCUUGAAGACCUCAUGACACCGGAGAUGGCAAAGGAGAGACGCGAAGAUUACCUCUGCUGGGUUAACAUGGCACAAUCUCGGCUCAAUGAACCCAUCAGCUCCCAGGUUUGAGGACUUCUCCGGCUUCCGCAUCCCGAGUAGCUGGGAUUACGGACGCCUGCCACCACACCCAGCUCAAAUCAUUUUAUGAAUGCAUAUUUCCAUCUGGGUGAAAAAAAAAUCACAAGCCUCUCUCUCUUCCUACUGAGCACCUGUGAACAGUGACCUGCAGUUUGUGGCUGCAGCCAGUCCUCAUGGAGCCUGCUGUUCUUACAUUUCAUUCUGAGGCUCACAUUCUCAGUCACCAUGCAGAAGAACACCCGCCCCAUCCUGGGUCAUUACAGAGUGGGCCAAUCCAUCUGCUGCAUCUGAGGAGCUGGGUCCAGCUUCUACGGUGAAUCCAUAUAUUUCUGUAUUUCCUGGAUAAGGAAGAGGAAAGGAGCUGAGCUGGUGGAGGAAGAAGAUCUAAUAUUAACUGACUCCUUAUUUUGUACCAGUCAAGGACGUGUCAACAUAGAGACUUAGGAGGACAAAGUGAACUUCCUGAUCCCCAACAGGCAGAUCCCCAAAAGCCAAAAUGUAUGUGUCACCUUGGAAGAUGACGCACCAGGAAGAAUGGGGAGGAGGGAGGAGGAAAAACUGCUGAUGAGGCCGACUCGCUCUUUGGGGCUUAUCAUAUCAGCAAAGCCAGCUCUUUUGAGAUGGAAGAACAAAGAUGUUUCUCCUCUGUGAGGAGGUGACAGUGGUGUUCUGGGUGAAGGAGAGCAGCUUUGUCCUGGAAGGAAUCUGACUUGGAAGGAGGCCCAGUUGUCCAGCAGUGGAUAUGACGUCAGAUAUUGACACAGCCAACAAUCGACUCAUCAUUUCUGAAGACCUGUGGAGUGUCCAUUGUGGAUUUCUUAGAACCGCACAGAGUAUGCCGAGAUUCAAACAAGUCAUCUGUGUCCUGGGCUCCCCUCGCUUCACCUCUGGACACCAUUACUGGGAGUGGACAUGGCUGCACUCUUCCAAGAAGCAAGCAGCUGUCCCGUCUGCUCAGACUAUCUAGAGAAACCAAUGUCCCUGGAGUGUGGAUGCGCUGUCUGCUUCAAGUGCAUCAAUUCACUGCAGAAGGAGCCCCAUGGGGAGGAUCUACUUUGCUGUUGCUGUUCCAUGGUCUCUCAGAAGAACAAAAUCAGGCCCAGUUGGCAGCUAGAGAGGCUGGCUUCCCACAUCAAGGAACUGGAGCCCAAGCUGAAGAAGAUUCUGCAGAUGAACCCAAGGAUGCGGAAGUUCCAAGUGGAUAUGACCUUGGAUGCCGACACAGCCAACAACUUCCUCCUCAUUUCUGACGACCUCAGGAGCGUCCGAAGUGGGUGCAUCACACAGAAUCGGCAAGACCUUGCCGAGAGAUUUGACGUGUCCAUUUGCAUCCUGGGCUCCCCUCGCUUUACCUGUGGCCGCCACUACUGGGAGGUGGACGUGGGAACAAGCACAGAAUGGGACCUGGGAGUCUGCAGAGAAUCUGUUCACCGCAAAGGGAGGAUCCAUCUGACCACAGAGCGUGGAUUCUGGACUGUGAGUUUGAGGGAUGGAAGCCGCCUCUCUGCCAGCACGGUGCCGCUGACUUUCCUCUUCGUAGACCGCAAGUUACAGCGAGUGGGGAUUUUUCUGGAUAUGGGCAUGCAGAACGUUUCCUUUUUUGAUGCUGAAGGUGGUUCCCAUGUCUAUACAUUCAGGAGUGUCUCUGCUGAGGAGCCACUGCACUUGUUUUUUGCUCCUCCAAGUCCACCUAAUGGUGAUAAGAGUGUCUUGAGUAUCUGUCCUGUGAUAAACCCGGGCACUACUGAUGCUCCAGUCCAUCCUGGGGAGGCCAAAUAAGCCCCCACUGCAAAAAAACAAAAAACAGGUUAAGAAAAUUACUUGGGUGGGCAGACUUAGGAACGCUCUACUCGGUAAAAGCGUUAUACAAAGUCAUAGGAGAAAAAUAUGGGACAAUUCAUGAUUAUACUUAAUCUAAUUUGAUUAGUUUAUAAAUUGAGUCCUAAGUAUUAAUUAUUGCCACCAUCCAACUCAUUGAGUCUUAUGGUUCACAUCUUGUUUCCUAUAGAAAUAUUCUGUAUUCUGGGAUCAAUUUCCAAAUGCUUUUUUAUUUCUGUAAGUUCAAAUUAAUGUAUUAUAGAAGUUAUGAGUUAAAUAAACAUUGGAAUAUCA